AGGAGCCCAGCUGGCUUCACCCAGUGGAUCACGCACUAGGGCUACAGGUGGAGCUGCUUGCCAGUCCGCCGCCGUGAGCCCACACUCCUCAGCCCUUGGGUGGUUGAUGGGACUGGGCGCUGUGGAGCAGCGGGCGGCGCUCGUCGCGGAGGCUCGGGCAUGGCGGGCUGCAGGUCCCUAGCCCUGCCCUGCAGGAAGACAGCUAAGGCCAGGCGAGAAAUUGAGCACGGCAGCUGCUGGCCCAGGUGCUAAGCCCCUCAACUGCCCGGGGCCGGUGGGGCCGGCAGGCGGCUCCGAGUUGCGAGGUCCGCGGGGCCCACGCCCACCCGGAACUCACGCUGGCCCGCAAGCACCGCGCGCAGCCCCGGUUCCUGCCCGCACCUCUCCCUCCACACCUCCCCGCAAGCUGAGGGAGCCGGCUCCGGCCUCGGCCAGCCCAGGAAGGCGCUCCCACAGCGCAGUGGUGGGCUGAAGGGCUCCUCAAGUGCCGCCAAAGUGGGAGCCCAGGCAGAGGAGGCGCCGAGAGCGAGGGAGGGCUGUGAGGACUGCCAGCACGCUGUCACCUCUCAAUAGCAGCCCAAACAGAUUAAGACAUGGGAGAUGUACAAGGGCAGCCGUGGGGCUGGCAACAGCUUCGUAAUCCUGGCUUCCUGCUUUCUGGGUCAAAGCCCUGGUGGUGUGUUCUUGAUAUCGGUCCAUCUAGUGGCGUUGUUUGAUUCCUCCCACCUUGCUGAUCAUUCGUAGUGUAGCCCCCAAGGUGAAAGACAACUUGAGUGGUUAAAUUACUGUCAUGCAAAGCGACUAGAUGGUUCAGCUGAUUGCACCUUUAGAAGUUAUGUGGAACGAGGCAGCAGAUCUUAAGCCCCUUGCUCUGUCACGCAGGCUGGAAUGCAGUGGUGGAAUCAUGGCUCACUACAGCCCUGACCUCCUGGGCCCAGAGAUGGAGUCUCGCUAUUUUGCCCAGGUUGGUCUUGAACACCUGGCUUCAAGCAGUCCUCCUGCUUUUGGCUUCUUGAAGUGCUUGGAUUACAGUAUUUCAGUUUUAUGCUCUGCAACAAGUUUGGCCAUGUUGGAGGACAAUCCAAAGGUCAGCAAGUUGGCUACUGGCGAUUGGAUGCUCACUCUGAAGCCAAAGUCUAUUACUGUGCCCGUGGAAAUCCCCAGCUCCCCUCUGGGUUGACAUUCGUAACCUUCCUGGAUCCUAUCAGAGAAACCUUGUUCAUCAUUUCAUUUCCAAAUUAUGAAGACCACCUGGGCCUGACUGAAGAUGCUUGUUUCUUCCUCUUCCCUAACGCCCUUUCCACCAGUGCGGACUGCAGAUUGUCAGUGGCUGCUAUGCAGCAGGUGCAGCCUGGUCUCUCACUGAGUCUCUACUCCACAAAGGCAACGACUGGCCAAGGCAGUGGCUGGCUCUGGGUUACACAAGUGCAGACACUCAACUAAGUGAGCUGGAAGACCCAGGAGAAGGCGGAGGCUCAGGUGCCCACAUGAUCAGCACAGCCAGGGUACCUGCUGACAAGCCUGUACGCAUCGCCUUUAGCCUCAAUGACGCCUCAGAUGAUACACCCCCUGAAGACUCCAUUCCUUUGGUCUUUCCAGAAUUAGACCAGCAGCUACAGCCCCUGCCGCCUUGUCAUGACUCCGAGGAAUCCAUGGAGGUGUUCAAACAGCACUGCCAAAUAGCAGAAGAAUACCAUGAGGUCAAAAAGGAAAUCACCCUGCUUGAGCAAAGGAAGAAGGAGCUCAUUGCCAAGUUAGAUCAGGCAGAAAAGGAGAAGGUGGAUGCUGCUGAGCUGGUUCGGGAAUUCGAGGCUCUGACGGAGGAGAAUCGGACGUUGAGGUUGGCCCAGUCUCAAUGUGUGGAACAACUGGAGAAACUUCGAAUACAGUAUCAGAAGAGGCAGGGCUCGUCCUAACUUUAAAUUUUUCAGUGUGAGCAUACGAGGCUGAUGACUGCCCUGUGCUGGCCAAAAGAUUUUUAUUUUAAAUGAAUAGUGAGUCAGAUCUAUUGCUUCUCUGUAUUACCCACAUGACAACUGUCUAUAAUGAGUUUACUGCUUGCCAGCUUCUAGCUUGAGAGAAGGGAUAUUUUAAAUGAGAUCAUUAACGUGAAACUAUUACUAGUAUAUGUUUUUGGAGAUCAGAAUUCUUUUCCAAAGAUAUAUGUUUUUUUCUUUUUUAGGAAGAUAUGAUCAUGCUGUACAACAGGGUAGAAAAUGAUAAAAAUAGACUAUUGACUGACCCAGCUAAGAAUCGUGGGCUGAGCAGAGUUAAACCAUGGGACAAACCCAUAACAUGUUCACCAUAGUUUCACGUAUGUGUAUUUUUAAAUUUCAUGCCUUUAAUAUUUCAAAUAUGCUCAAAUUUAAACUGUCAGAAACUUCUGUGCAUGUAUUUAUAUUUGCCAGAGUAUAAACUUUUAUACUCUGAUUUUUAUCCUUCAAUGAUUGAUUAUACUAAGAAUAAAUGGUCACAUAUCCUAAAAGCUUCUUCAUGAAAUUAUUAGCAGAAACCAUGUUUGUAACCAAAGCACAUUUGCCAAUGCUAACUGGCUGUUGUAAUAAUAAACAGAUAAGGCUGCAUUUGCUUCAUGCCAUGUGACCUCACAGUAAACAUCUCUGCCUUUGCCUGUGUGUGUUCUGGGGGAGGGGGGACAUGGAAAAAUAUUGUUUGGACAUUACUUGGGUGAGUGCCCAUGAAAACAUCAGUGAACUUGUAACUAUUGUUUUGUUUUGGAUUUAAGGAGAUGUUUUAGAUCAGUAACAGCUAAUAGGAAUAUGCGAGUAAAUUCAGAAUUGAAACAAUUUCUCCUUGUUCUACCUAUCACCACAUUUUCUCAAAUUGAACUCUUUGUUAUAUGUCCAUUUCUAUUCAUGUAACUUCUUUUUCAUUAAACAUGGAUCAAAACUGA